ACACUCAGCCACUGCGGGCGAGGAGGGCACAAGGCCAGGUUCCCAAGAGCUCAGGUGAGUGACACACCGGAAUGGCCCAGGACGCCCUCACCCUGCUCAGCUUGUGGCUCCAACAUUCCAGAAGCCGAGGCCUCUGCUAUCCCUGCCCUCUCCCCAUGGAUAUCCCAUUUCAGACAACCCCGGCCGGCCUGAAUCCCCCUCCCUUCCUUUUUUUUUUUUCCGGGGAGGCCAGGUCUUGCUGUCACCGAGGCUGGAGUGCUGUGGGAUCCUGGCCACUGCAGCCUUGAAUUCCUGGGCUCAAGUGAUUCUCCUGCCUCAGUAGCUAGGACUACAGACCCUCACCAUCCUGCCUGGAUAGUUUUAAAAAAUAUUUUUAAAAGAUUUUUAGAGAUGGGGUCUUCCAAUGCUGCCCAGAUUGGUCUCCAAAUUCUGGCCUCAGCCUCCCUAGGGUCUGGGAUUACAGGUGGGAGCCACCCUGCCCAGGAUCCUCCUUUUGCUGAGUCAUCACAGUUUUGCUCAUUCCCACAUCAGGCUCUGGCCCCCAAUACCAGCUCAGUUGCUCAAUGGGCUGUUUGUCCUGGAGCCCAGAUGGACUGUGGCCGGGCAAGUGGAUCACAGGCCUGGCCAGCCUAGGAGUUGCCACAUGUGAGGGGCCGAGGGGCUCAAGGAGGGGAACAUCGGGGAGAGGAGCCUACUGGGUGGAGGCUGGGGGUCCCAGCAGGAAAUGGUGAGACAAAGGGCGCUGGCUGGCAGGAAGACAGCACAGGAAGGUCCUAGAGGUUCCUCAGUGCAGCUGGACUCUCCUGGAGACCUUCACACACCCUGACAUCUGGGCCCCGCGCCACGAGGGUGCUUUCACUGGUCUGCACCAUGGCCCAGGCCCUGGGAUUUUGAACAGCUCCGCAGGUGAAUGAAAGGAACAUGGAGCUGAUCCAGGACAUCUCUCGCCCGCCACUGGAGUACGUGAAGGGGGUCCCGCUCAUCAAGUACUUUGCAGAGGCACUGGGGCCCCUGCAGAGCUUCCAGGCCCGGCCUGAUGACCUGCUCAUCAGCACCUACCCCAAGUCCGGCACCACCUGGGUGAGCCAGAUUCUGGACAUGAUCUACCAGGGCGGUGACCUGGAAAAGUGUCACCGAGCUCCCAUCUUCAUGCGGGUGCCCUUCCUUGAGUUCAAAGUCCCAGGGAUUCCCUCAGGGAUGGAGACUCUGAAAAACACACCAGCCCCACGACUCCUGAAGACACACCUGCCCCUGGCUCUGCUCCCCCAGACUCUGUUGGAUCAGAAGGUCAAGGUGGUCUAUGUUGCCCGCAACGCAAAGGAUGUGGCGGUUUCCUACUACCACUUCUACCACAUGGCCAAAGUGUACCCUCACCCUGGGACCUGGGAAAGCUUCCUGGAGAAGUUCAUGGCUGGAGAAGUGUCCUAUGGGUCCUGGUACCAGCACGUGCAAGAGUGGUGGGAGCUGAGCCGCACCCACCCUGUUCUCUACCUCUUCUAUGAAGACAUGAAGGAGAACCCCAAAAGGGAGAUUCAAAAGAUCCUGGAGUUUGUGGGGCGCUCCCUGCCAGAGGAGACUGUGGACCUCAUGGUUGAGCACACGUCGUUCAAGGAGAUGAAGAAGAACCCUAUGACCAACUACACCACCGUCCGCCGGGAGUUCAUGGACCACAGCAUCUCCCCCUUCAUGAGGAAAGGCAUGGCUGGGGACUGGAAGACCACCUUCACCGUGGCGCAGAAUGAGCGCUUCGAUGCGGACUAUGCGAAGAAGAUGGCAGGCUGCAGCCUCAGCUUCCGCUCUGAGCUGUGAGAGGGGUUCCUGGAGUCACUGCAGAGGGAGUGUGCGAAUCAAGCCUGACCAAGAGGCUCCAGAAUAAAGUAUGAUUUGUGUUCAA